AGUCGGCCUGCGCUCCUCAGCCUGGCGGUUCUACCUCCGAGGGUUCGCCCGCCCUUGGUUUUCCUUACACCUUAGCCUUUGGCUCCUUUGACCACUCGAAGCCCCACAGCGUGUUCCAGCGGACUUCACCAGCAGACCCAGAAGUGGUGGGUGAAACACUGCCUCUGUUCCUCCUUGAGCCUGUCGGGAGCUGCUGCCUGCCACCACCAUGUCUGCUGCAAAUCCUGAGACUCCAAACUCAACCAUCUCCAGAGAGGCCAGCACCCAGUCUUCAUCAGCUGCAGCUAGCCAAGGCUGGGUGUUACCAGAAGGCAAAAUCGUGCCAAACACUGUUUUUGUUGGUGGAAUUGAUGCUAGGAUGGAUGAAACUGAGAUUGGAAGCUGCUUUGGUAGAUACGGUUCAGUGAAAGAAGUGAAGAUAAUCACGAAUCGAACUGGUGUGUCCAAAGGCUAUGGAUUUGUUUCGUUUGUUAAUGACGUGGAUGUCCAGAAGAUAGUAGGAUCACAGAUACAUUUCCAUGGUAAAAAGCUGAAGCUGGGCCCUGCAAUCAGGAAACAAAAGUUAUGUGCUCGUCAUGUGCAGCCACGUCCUUUGGUAGUUAAUCCUCCUCCUCCACCACAGUUUCAGAACGUCUGGCGGAAUCCAAACACUGAAACCUACCUGCAGCCCCAAAUCACGCCGAAUCCUGUAACUCAGCACGUUCAGGCUUAUUCUGCUUAUCCACAUUCACCAGGUCAGGUCAUCACUGGAUGUCAGUUGCUUGUAUAUAAUUAUCAGGAAUAUCCUACUUAUCCCGAUUCAGCAUUUCAGGUCACCACUGGAUAUCAGUUGCCUGUAUAUAAUUAUCAGCCAUUUCCUGCUUAUCCAAGAUCACCAUUUCAGGUCACUGCUGGAUAUCAGUUGCCUGUAUAUAAUUAUCAGGCAUUUCCUGCUUAUCCAAAUUCACCAUUUCAAGUCGCCACUGGAUAUCAGUUCCCUGUAUACAAUUAUCAGCCAUUUCCUGCUUAUCCAAGUUCACCAUUUCAGGUCACUGCUGGAUAUCAGUUGCCUGUAUAUAAUUAUCAGGCAUUUCCUGCUUAUCCAAAUUCACCAUUUCAAGUCGCCACUGGAUAUCAGUUCCCUGUAUACAAUUAUCAGCCAUUUCCUGCUUAUCCAAGUUCACCAUUUCAGGUCACUGCUGGAUAUCAGUUGCCUGUAUAUAAUUAUCAGGCAUUUCCUGCUUAUCCAAAUUCACCAUUUCAAGUCGCCACUGGAUAUCAGUUCCCUGUAUACAAUUAUCAGGCAUUUCCUGCUUAUCCAAAUUCACCAGUUCAGGUCACCACUGGAUAUCAGUUGCCUGUAUACAAUUAUCAGCCAUUUCCUGCUUAUCCAAGAUCACCAUUUCAGGUCACUGCUGGAUAUCAGUUGCCUGUAUAUAAUUAUCAGGCAUUUCCUGCUUAUCCAAAUUCACCAUUUCAAGUCGCCACUGGAUAUCAGUUCCCUGUAUACAAUUAUCAGGCAUUUCCUGCUUAUCCAAAUUCACCAGUUCAGGUCACCACUGGAUAUCAGUUGCCUGUAUACAAUUAUCAGGCAUUUCCUGCUUAUCCAAGUUCACCAUUUCAGGUCACCACUGGAUAUCAGUUGCCUGUAUAUAAUUAUCAGGCAUUUCCUGCUUAUCCAAGUUCACCAUUUCAGGUCACCACUGGAUAUCAGUUGCCUGUAUAUAAUUAUCAGGCAUUUCCUGCUUAUCCAAGUUCACCAUUUCAGGUCACCACUGGAUAUCAGUUGCCUGUAUAUAAUUAUCAGGCAUUUCCUGCUUAUCCAAGUUCACCAUUUCAGGUCACCACUGGAUAUCAGUUGCCUGUAUAUAAUUAUCAGGCAUUUCCUGCUUAUCCAAGUUCACCAUUUCAGGUCACCACUGGAUAUCAGUUGCCUGUAUAUAAUUAUCAGGCAUUUCCUGCUUAUCCAAGUUCACCAUUUCAGGUCACCACUGGAUAUCAGUUGCCUGUAUAUAAUUAUCAGGCAUUUCCUGCUUAUCCAAAUUCAGCAGUUCAGGUCACCACUGGAUAUCAGUUCCAUGUAUACAAUUACCAGAUGCCACCGCAGUGCCCUGUUGGGGAGCAAAGGAGAAAUCUGUGGACCGAAGCAUACAAAUGGUGGUAUCUUGUCUGUUUAAUCCAGAGAAGAGACUGAUAAAUUCCGUUGUUACUCAAGAUGACUGCUUCAAGGGUAAAAGAGUGCAUCGCUUUAGAAGAAGUUUGGCAGUAUUUAAAUCUGUUGGAUCCUCUCAGCUAUCUAGUUUCAUGGGAAGUUGCUGGUUUUGAAUAUUAAGCUAAAAGUUUUCCACUAUUACAGAAAUUCUGAAUUUUGGUAAAUCACACUGAAACUUUCUGUAUAACUUGUAUUAUUAGACUCUCUAGUUUUAUCUUAACACUGAAACUGUUCUUCAUUAGAUGUUUAUUUAGAACCUGGUUCUGUGUUUAAUAUAUAGUUUAAAGUAACAAAUAAUCGAGACUGAAAGAAUGUUAAGAUUUAUCUGCAAGGAUUUUUAAAAAAUUGAAACUUGCAUUUUAAGUGUUUAAAAGCAAAUACUGACUUUCAAAAAAGUUUUUAAAACCUGAUUUGAAAGCUAACAAUUUUGAUAGUCUGAACACAAGCAUUUCACUUCUCCAAGAAGUACCUGUGAACAGUACAAUAUUUCAGUAUUGAGCUUUGCAUUUAUGAUUUAUCUAGAAAUUUACCUCAAAAGCAGAAUUUUUAAAACUGCAUUUUUAAUCAGUGGAACUCAAUGUAUAGUUAGCUUUAUUGAAGUCUUAUCCAAACCCAGUAAAACAGAUUCUAAGCAAACAGUCCAAUCAGUGAGUCAUAAUGUUUAUUCAAAGUAUUUUAUCUUUUAUCUAGAAUCCACAUAUGUAUGUCCAAUUUGAUUGGGAUAGUAGUUAGGAUAACUAAAAUUCUGGGCCUAAUUUUUUAAAGAAUCCAAGACAAACUAAACUUUACUGGGUAUAUAACCUUCUCAAUGAGUUACCAUUCUUUUUUAUAAAAAAAAUUGUUCCUUGAAAUGCUAAACUUAAUGGCUGUAUGUGAAAUUUGCAAAAUACUGGUAUUAAAGAACGCUGCAGCUUUUUUAUGUCACUCAAAGGUUAAUCGGAGUAUCUGAAAGGAAUUGUUUUUAUAAAAACAUUGAAGUAUUAGUUACUUGCUAUAAAUAGAUUUUUAUUUUUGUUUUUUAGCCUGUUAUAUUUCCUUCUGUAAAAUAAAAUAUGUCCAGAAGAGGCAUGUUGUUUCUAGAUUAGGUAGUGUCCUCAUUUUAUAUUGUGACCACACAGCUAGAGCACCAGAGCCCUUUUGCUAUACUCACAGUCUUGUUUUCCCAGCCUCUUUUACUAGUCUUUCAGGAGGUUUGCUCUUAGAACUGGUGAUGUAAAGAAUGGAAGUAGCUGUAUGAGCAGUUCAAAGGCCAAGCCGUGGAAUGGUAGCAAUGGGAUAUAAUACCUUUCUAAGGGAAACAUUUGUAUCAGUAUCAUUUGAUCUGCCAUGGACAUGUGUUUAAAGUGGCUUUCUGGCCCUUCUUUCAAUGGCUUCUUCCCUAAAACGUGGAGACUCUAAGUUAAUGUCGUUACUAUGGGCCAUAUUACUAAUGCCCACUGGGGUCUAUGAUUUCUCAAAAUUUUCAUUCGGAAUCCGAAGGAUACAGUCUUUAAACUUUAGAAUUCCCAAGAAGGCUUUAUUACACCUCAGAAAUUGAAAGCACCAUGACUUUGUCCAUUAAAAAAUUAUCCAUAGUUUUUUUAGUGCUUUUAACAUUCCGACAUACAUCAUUCUGUGAUUAAAUCUCCAGAUUUCUGUAAAUGAUACCUACAUUCUAAAGAGUUAAUUCUAAUUAUUCCGAUAUGACCUUAAGGAAAAGUAAAGGAAUAAAUUUUUGUCUUUGUUGAAGUAUUUAAUAGAGUAAGGUAAAGAAGAUAUUAAGUCCCUUUCAAAAUGGAAAAUUAAUUCUAAACUGAGAAAAAUGUUCCUACUACCUAUUGCUGAUACUGUCUUUGCAUAAAUGAAUAAAAAUAAACUUUUUUUCUUCAAAUGUG